UCAAGUAGUAUAGCGUAGUAGGAUUGAAUAAUAAAGUGCAACUGUCUCACCUGUCCUACUCUCAGUACUGUUCUUCAAAGAUAACCACUUUUAACCUUUUCUAAUUUUAGGUCUGUAGGUUAAAUAAUAAGUUAAACUGUUAAUUCUUUUUGUUGACUUCUUGAGAUAGCCCUAAGUUGAACUGCUAAUUCUUUUUCCGUUGACUUCUAGAAAUAGCCCACACCAUUCACAAUCUCCUCUGAAUUUUGGAAGAGUCAUAAUCAUAAUUUUUAGUUUUUGUAUUGGUUACUUUAUAAUUCAAAAUAAUAUACGUAAACUACUUUUUUCACAUCAACUUUUGAAAAUAUAUUUGACUCCUUGUUUGGUAAAACGAGAAAAGUAGUGAUUCUACCUUUUUCUUUAUCACUUCAGAAACUACAUUUAUGCCCACUUUCUCUUAGCUGGACAUUUACUUGUACAUUGUCAAAGUUAGUAAUAUAUUUCUUAACUAUAACAUUUGCGCUUUAUUCACGUGCCAAAAACCAAUAAAAAAAAUAAAAUGUUUACAGUAUUAUGGCUUUAUAGUUGUUACUUAGAGCAAGUCCAAGCUGUAUGCUCUGAUAUGUUUUUUUCCCCAGAGUUUUAACUUCAUGAUCCCUGUGCCAUACUAAGGAGAUUAUUUAUGAUAUCAAGGUCAAAUGGGUUUUUAUUUCUUUCCUGCCAAGGGCAAAAUAUGCUGUAGUUGAGCAUGCUUUAUAUUUUGGAGUAUGUAAUACAUAGUUUUUAACCGUCCCCACUUUCUUAAUUGCCUUUCUGCUUUCUCCUGGGGAAUAGGUAGGUGGAUGUGCUUUCUUCACUGAAUCUUCUCAUUCUUUGUAUGAUGCACAUAGAAGCAAGCUUCCAUUCCUCUGUUUGAAGAUUUUCCCCUUAAAGCCCAAUGGCUUUCUGUUUAAUUUGAACAGAUUGCAUUCUAGUCCUUUUGUAUUGCUCCUAUCCUGGGCUUAUAUUCAUUCUUGGGUAAAUAACAUUGUUUCUUAGCCCCUCAUCUUCUGUUAUUGGGCUUCCCCCUAUUUCCCUGGAAUAUAUCCUAAGGAAACUUGCUCACAAAAGGCAAGUGAAAGGUAAUUUUAUUUUUUAAUGUUCGUAUAGCUGUAAAUUAUAAUUUGCUCUUAUGACUGAUAAUUUGGCUGUAUAUAGAAUCAAAAGUAUUUUCCUUCAACUCUCAAUCCUUCCAUGUCUUCUAACUUUUUUUUUUUCCUUUUUUUUGAGCUGGAGUCUCACUGUGUUGCUCAGUCUGGUCUGAAACUCCUGACCUCACGUGAUCCUCCCACCUCAGCCUCUCAAGUAUCUGGGAUCACAGGCACAAGCCACUGCACCAGGCUCUCUUCUGACUUUCAUUAUUGCUGAUGAGAAUGCCAGUCUCACUUUAACUUGUUGAUAGCAGAAUCAGUUUUUUCUGUCUGAAAUGUUUACAAUUUUCUAGUUACGUUUGAUGCUUUGAAAAUGUAUAGCAGUGUUUAUCUUCUCAUAAGCUGUUUUAUUUUGUGUGAGAUAAAAUUUGAUACAUAUUAAAACACAUUGAUUUUAAGUGGCCAAUUUAAUGAGUUUUGAUGCAUGUACUCAUCCAUAAAACCACUACCACCACAAUCGAGAUAGAGAAUAUUUCUACCACUACAGAAAGUUCCUCUGUUUCUCUGCUUAUUCAACCCCUCUCCCCCAUCUACAGUACUAUCUUCUGAUUUUUUUAUUAAUACUAUAGUUUAGAACUAUAGUUCUGGAAUUACAUUUAAAUGGAGUCAUACAGUAUGAACUCUUUUGUGUCUGCUUCUUUCAUAAACUUUAUGUUUUUGAGUAUAUCCAUGUUUUGACAUGUUUGUUCCAUUUUUGUUAAAUAGAAUUUCAUGGUACAAAUAUGUUAAUUGAUUCACUUAUGGGACAUUUGCAUUGCUUCUGGUUUUUAGCUAUUAAGAGUACAGUUCCUAUGAACAUACUCAUACAGUGUUUUUUUUUAUGGACAAAUGUUUUCAUUUUUCUUGGUUAAAGAGUGGAAUUUCUGAGUCAUAAGUUAGGGAUAUUUUUAACUUUAGAAAAGUUUUCCAAAUAUUUUCCAAAAUUCUUUUGCCAUUUUACGCUCCCACUAGCAAUAUAGCAAAGCUCCACUUCCACAUUCUCAACACUUGUUACUGCCAGUCAUUUAAAUUUUAGCCAUUGUAGAAGUUAAAGGUUUGUCAUUGUGAUUUUCAUUUGCAUUUCCCCCAAUUAAUGAUAUUAAGAACUUUUUCAUGUGCUUAUUAUUUUCAUGCCUUGUGUGAAAAUAUGUUUGUGACUUUUACCUAUUUAUGUAUUGGCUUGUUUUAUUAUUGAAUUGUGGUAUUUCUUUAUAGACUCCGAAUACAGGUCAAUUAUAUACAGACACACAUAUGUUUGAUUUUAAAAGGUCAUAUAUAUACAUAAUGUCAUAUGUAUAUACAGACAGAUGUAAAUAAUAUUUCCCUUUAACUCGAAUUUUUAUUUUCUCAGGGGUGCCUUUGGAUAUGCAGAUGUUUUUAAUUUUGAUGAAGUCUACUUUGUCAAAAUUGUCUUUUGUGGCUAGUGCUUUGUUCUAUUGUGUCUAAGAAAUCUUUGCCUAGCCUAAGGUUGUAAAGAUAUUCGCUUAUGUUUUCAAUUAGAAGACUAACAGUUUUACCUUUUACGCUUAAGCCUAUGUUCCAUCUUAGAUUUUUGUGGAUGUAUCAGUAGAAGUUGAGGUUAUUAUUUUUUUAUAUGAAUAUCUUUUUCCAGCACCAUUUGUAAAAAGGACUUUCCUUUUCCUGUUGAACUCUUUUGCUUUUGUUGAGAAUCAAUUUAUUUUAUUUAAAUUCUUUUAAUUAUGAAAUAUGUGGUAUUAACACACACAUAUGUAGAUAAAUAUAGAUACAGAGCAUGGAAAUUACCAAGCAUAAUGAUAACAUGAACACCCAUUAAUUCACCAGCUAAAAACUAGGCUAUUACUCAAGAUUUUUGAAGCUUUUUAUGAAUUUUUCCCUAACCUUACCCCACUUUAAUUUGGUAGUAACCCAUAUUCUGAGUAUUUUUUUUAAAUUCCCUUACUUAUUGAAUAUAUUCUUACAAUAGAUAUAAGUAUUCCAGAAUUAUUUGUUUUAUUUUUUGUUUUUGAGUUUUAUGAAAACUGGAAUAUUUUAUGUUACUUUUUUCACUCAAUAUUAUAUUUCUAAGAUUCAUCUAUGCUAUUAAAUAUGGCUAUAGUUUGCUUAUUUUUCAUUAUGUAUACAGGUGAAUAAAGCACAAUUUAUUUAACCAUUUACCUACCAUUGGACAUUUAAAUUGUCUCCAGCUUGGGGAUAUUAGGAGCAAUAAUACUGCCUUGAUCUUUCUUGCACAGGUCCACUCUGUGUGUGUGUGUGUGUGUGUGUGUGUGUGUGUGUGUGUGUGUGUGUAGGAGUUUCUGUAGGAAUAUAAUAGCAAGAUAGUGUAAAACAUAUCUAGUGAUUUUACUAAUUUACACUCCCACUUACAGCAAAUUAGAGAUCCUAUUUUUCCACAUCCUUCUAACAUUAUGUGUUAUCAGAUUUCUUAAUUUUUGACUGUCCAGUAGAUAAAAAUUUUUUGUGGUUUUAAUGUGCAAUUCCUUGAUUAUUCAUGAGGUUGUUUAUCUUCUCAUGUAUCUAUUGGCCAUUUCUCUUUAUUCUUUUGUAUAAUGUGUUUUUCUAUAACUUGUUUUAUGUAAUGGAUGCAAUAUCUCCUCAAAUCUCUCUAUGUUUGUUAGAGUUGGUUUUUGUGUUAUUUUUUCAUAAAUUAUUUCAGUUGCUUCCAAAGCCAGAUUUUUGGAGGUUUAUUUCAUUGUUUGCCCUUGAUACUGUAGUCUUUCCUCAACUAUCUGAUGAUUCUCAGACAACUCAUUAUUUAAGAGCUAAGGCUUCCUGGGAGCUUUGCAUAUAUGGACAGGCUUAUUGACGGAUAUAUUUUGUUUUAGGAUGGCUGGGUGAACAGCCAAAUCUUAGCUGGGGUCCUACAAAUUCCGGAAUUGUGAGGAGUUUGCUCUUCUCACCAGUGUCCAUAGCAACUAGUGUAGUUCUCAGUUUGUUCAGCUUCUUUAGGGAAGAACCUUAUCUUUUUCUUUUUUUCAUGGAGUGUAAAUAACUGCCAAUGUUGUGGGGCUGGUGGCAGAAUUGACGCUUCUAAUUAUUCAACACUUCACCCUUCUGAUUUCAAACCCUCUGACUGCUGUUUAACAUUGUUCCCGCCUUCUCUGAGUCUGAAGCCUCUGAAUCUGAAGGGACCAAACAAACCUCUUGACUAUUACAGAUUAUCUUAGAAGACCUAGGACUCCAAAAAUGUUUCCCCUGAAGGACGCUGAAAUGGGAGCCUUUACCUUCUUUGCCUCGGCUCUGCCACAUGAUGUUUGUGGAAGCAAUGGACUUCCUCUCACACCAAAUUCCAUCAAAAUUUUAGGGCGCUUUCAAAUCCUUAAAACCAUCACCCAUCCCAGACUCUGCCAGUAUGUGGAUAUUUCUAGGGGAAAGCAUGAACGACUAGUGGUCGUGGCUGAACAUUGUGAACGUAGUCUGGAAGACUUGCUUCGAGAAAGGAAACCUGUGAGCUGUUCAACGGUUUUGUGUAUAGCAUUUGAGGUUCUUCAGGGCUUGCAGUAUAUGAACAAACAUGGUAUAGUACACAGGGCAUUGUCUCCUCAUAAUAUCCUGUUGGACCGAAAGGGACAUAUUAAAUUGGCUAAAUUUGGACUUUAUCACAUGACAGCUCAUGGUGAUGAUGUUGAUUUCCCAAUAGGGUAUCCCUCGUACUUGGCCCCUGAGGUAAUUGCACAGGGAAUUUUCAAAACCACUGAUCACAUGCCAAGUAAAAAACCAUUGCCUUCUGGCCCCAAAUCAGAUGUAUGGUCUCUUGGAAUCAUUUUAUUUGAGCUUUGUGUGGGAAGAAAAUUAUUUCAGAGCUUGGAUAUUUCUGAAAGACUAAAAUUUUUGCUUACUUUGGAUUGUGUAGAUGACACUUUAAUAGUUCUGGCUGAAGAGCAUGGUUGUUUGGACAUUAUAAAGGAGCUUCCUGAAACUGUGAUAGAUCUUUUGAAUAAGUGCCUUACCUUCCAUCCUUCUAAGAGGCCAACCCCAGAUCAAUUAAUGAAGGACAAAGUAUUCAGUGAGGUAUCACCUUUAUAUACCCCCUUUACCAAACCUGCCAGUCUGUUUUCAUCUUCUCUGAGAUGUGCUGAUUUAACUCUGCCUGAGGAUAUCAGUCAGUUGUGUAAAGAUAUAAAUAAUGAUUACCUGGCAGAAAGAUCUAUUGAAGAAGUGUAUUACCUUUGGUGUUUGGCUGGAGGUGACUUGGAGAAAGAGCUUGUCAACAAGGAAAUCAUUCGAUCCAAACCACCUAUCUGCACACUCCCCAAUUUUCUCUUUGAGGAUGGUGAAAGCUUUGGACAAGGUCGAGAUAGAAGCUCGCUUUUAGAUGAUACCACUGUGACAUUGUCGUUAUGCCAGCUAAGAAAUAGAUUGAAAGAUGUUGGUGGAGAAGCAUUUUACCCAUUACUUGAAGAUGACCAGUCUAAUUUACCUCAUUCAAACAGCAAUAAUGAGUUGUCUGCAGCUGCCACGCUCCCUUUAAUCAUCAGAGAGAAGGAUACAGAGUACCAACUAAAUAGAAUUAUUCUCUUCGACAGGCUGCUAAAGGCUUAUCCAUAUAAAAAAAACCAAAUCUGGAAAGAAGCAAGAGUUGACAUUCCUCCUCUUAUGAGAGGUUUAACCUGGGCUGCUCUUCUGGGAGUUGAGGGAGCUAUUCAUGCCAAGUACGAUGCAAUUGAUAAAGACACUCCAAUUCCUACAGAUAGACAAAUUGAAGUGGAUAUUCCUCGCUGUCAUCAGUACGAUGAACUGUUAUCAUCACCAGAAGGUCAUGCAAAAUUUAGGCGUGUAUUAAAAGCCUGGGUAGUGUCUCAUCCUGAUCUUGUGUAUUGGCAAGGUCUUGACUCACUUUGUGCUCCAUUCCUAUAUCUAAACUUCAAUAAUGAAGCCUUGGCUUAUGCAUGUAUGUCUGCUUUUAUUCCCAAAUACCUGUAUAACUUCUUCUUAAAAGACAACUCACAUGUAAUACAAGAGUAUCUGACUGUCUUCUCUCAGAUGAUUGCAUUUCAUGAUCCAGAGCUGAGUAAUCAUCUCAAUGAGAUUGGUUUCAUUCCAGAUCUCUAUGCCAUCCCUUGGUUUCUUACCAUGUUUACUCAUGUAUUUCCACUACACAAAAUUUUCCACCUCUGGGAUACCUUACUACUUGGGAAUUCCUCUUUCCCAUUCUGUAUUGGAGUAGCAAUUCUUCAGCAGCUGCGGGACCGGCUUUUGGCUAAUGGCUUUAAUGAGUGUAUUCUUCUCUUCUCCGAUUUACCAGAAAUUGACAUUGAACGCUGUGUGAGAGAAUCUAUCAACCUGUUUUGUUGGACUCCUAAAAGUGCUACUUACAGACAGCAUGCUCAACCUCCAAAGCCAUCUUCUGACAGCAGUGGAGGCAGAAGUUCGGCACCUUAUUUCUCUGCUGAGUGUCCAGAUCCUCCAAAGACAGAUCUGUCAAGAGAAUCCAUCCCAUUAAAUGACCUGAAGUCAGAAGUAUCACCACGGAUUUCAGCAGAGGACCUGAUUGACUUGUGUGAGCUCACAGUGACAGGCCACUUCAAAACACCCAGCAAGAAAACAAAGUCCAGUAAACCAAAGCUCCUGGUGGUUGACAUCCGGAAUAGUGAAGACUUUAUUCGUGGUCACAUUUCAGGAAGCAUCAACAUUCCAUUCAGUGCUGCCUUCACUGCAGAAGGGGAGCUUACCCAGGGCCCUUACACUGCUAUGCUCCAGAACUUCAAAGGGAAGGUCAUUGUCAUCGUGGGGCAUGUGGCAAAACACACAGCUGAGUUUGCAGCUCACCUUGUGAAGAUGAAAUAUCCAAGAAUCUGUAUUCUAGAUGGUGGCAUUAAUAAAAUAAAGCCAACAGGCCUCCUCACCAUCCCAUCUCCUCAAAUAUGAAGAACCAAGAGUGUGACUGCCAAAACUUAGUGUGGCAUCAGCACCAACAGCACAGUUCUUCAUAUCCACGCCACUCUCAGACAAAACUAGAUGUCCAGAUUGUUGCAUUUCCGUAAAGUUUGUCACGAGACAUUUUUUAAAAUCUCAUAACCCACAUGUUCAGUUAUCCAUGCAAGAAACUUGACUCUACAUGUAUUGCUGAAAGAAUUUUCUUAACAGUGAAAUCUGAUCAUAUAUUUUUACCACACUGCCACAUAAAGCCCAAGAAAUUCAGCUGACAAGACAGAUUUAGCAUUAUCAAGAAAUCCCAUUUGCCCUGAAAAAGCUGUCCUCCAUUGUACUGAACAGACAGUCCUGUCGAUUGUGUUAUUUAGAAACAUACACUGAAUGUGGGCUGAAAUCAUCAUCUUUCCAUAAUGAAAACUGAGAAACUAUUCACAAUGCAUUCCUUAUAAAUAAAUGCUACAUUUAGUAACUCAUUUCACCCAAACAAGGGGGAUGUGUGUGUGUGUGUGUGUAUAGGAAGUGGAGUUUAUCCCAUUGCAGAAAGUGGUAAUACUUACUCCCAGAAAAAUGAAAUUUAGAAACCAUUUAUAUUUGAUAGAAUAUUUGGUCAGUUCCUGUAGCAAAGACGAAUGGCUUAAACAAAUUUUCUAGUUUCUUUAUCACAUGAAAGUCUGUACAGUCAGUCCAGGGCUAGUCUACUGGUUUCCUGAUCAUUAAGAACUCAUUACCUUCUCUCAUUGCUUUACAAACCUCAAUAUGUGGCAUCCAUCUCAUGGAUGAAAAUGGCUCCUCAGCUUCUACCAUCACAUCUGCUAUCUAGAAGGAAGAGAAUGAGGGAAGGAGGGAGGGGAUGAAGAGAAAAGAAGGAACAAAAGAAGGAGGGAGGAAAGAAGAAAAGAAAGGAAAAGAAGCGAAGCACACUCCUUCCCUUUAAGGUCAUAAACCAGAAGUUGCGCACACUACCUCUGCUUACAUAUCAUUGGCCAGAACUUGGGUGCAUGGCCACACCUAGCUUUAAGGAAAACUGGAAAUAGAGUCUUUGGGUGGUUGAUCAUUUCCCCAGCUAAAAACAUUCUUAUUACUGUGUGGGAAGAAGAGAGUACAUAUUGAGGUACAGCUAACAACCUCUGCCUCUGCCACAUUGUUUUUAAAAUGAGUAUUAUAUUUCAUUAAAUCUAAGACAUCUCACAAUUUUAGGUACCACAAAGAAAAAAUGAAGCCAAAUGAAUUGUGACACUUUGUCAAUUAAAAGACACAUUCCCUGGGAGGCCGAGGUCAGGAGUUUGAGACCAGCCUGGCCAACAUGGGGAAACUUUGUCUCUACUAAAAAUAUAAAAAUUAGCUGGUCAUAGUGGCACACGUCUGCGGUCCCAGCUACUCAGGAGGCUGAGGCAGGAGAAUCACUUGAACCUGAGAGGCAGAGGUUGCAAUGAGCCAUGAUAGGGCCACUGUACCCCAGCCUGGGCAACAGGGCUCACCCUGCCAUCUCAAAAAAAAAAAAAAAAAGAAAGAUACAUUCCCAUUUCAGAAAUCUGAAAAAAAAAAUGCCUCAUAUAUAUGAAAUAUAGCAUAUCCUUUAAUUAUCUUCAAUUUUGUUUUAACUAAAAAGUGUUCAUUCAUCUAUAACUUACAUUCCACUCCAAUGUUAAGACUGCCUAGGCAGAACAUUUCAAUAAGAGCCUCAAUUCAGCUUUCUGGGCCAUGGUUUUGUUGUUGCUGCUAUUGUUUACUUUAUUUUAUUUUUUCUUUGCAUCUACUUUUUAAAUUGAGAUAUACUUAACCAUAAAAUUCAUCCUUUUAACAUGUACAGUUCAGUAGUUUUUAGUGUAUUCACAAAGUUGUGCAAUCAGUAUUAUCCAGAAUACUUUCAUUGUAUGCAAUUGUCUACCUGAUCAGCAGGUAUUCCACAUUAACCCCUCCUAAGGUCUUUGAUAAAUUUUUGUAUAUGGAGUGAGGGGUCCAGGUUCAUUCUUGCAUAUGAGUAUCCAGUUGUCCCAGGACCCCUCCUGUUUUGUUUGUUUUAUUCAAUUUAUUUGGUCAUUCACCAAAUAUGUUUUGAAUACCUACUAUGUAUUUCUAAGACACUAAUAUAAUCCAUAGUUAUAUCAUUUGUGAUCCUUACCUAGUUUACAAGGAAAAAAAUGUGAGAAUUAAUGAGAACAAAUAUAUACCAAGAUUUCACUAACAUUGUUUUUGGGCCAUUGUCUACCCUCUUCAGAGAAAUAUUAAAUCCUCCUGUCCUGGCAAUUACUAUUUUCUUCCUUCAGUCUUUGAUGACUUACCUGAGUUCAUAAUCAGAAUGCACCAUUGAUGAUCAUUCUGAGUCUUAACUCUGCCUUACUGAGAAAGCAGAGAAGAGAGGGAUGGAGGGGCAGUGAUUUGAGUUGAAUAAGGUGGUAGGUAGUAGGAGAGGAUGAAGACCUUGUGAAGAGAGCUAUGUAAGAAGAUAAUAGUAGCAACCCUCUGUCAUGAUUUUGCAUUUGAUCUUUCUUAAAACGACACAUUUAGGCUUAUUCCAAGAAAUUGAAGUUUUUUAAACAUGAAAAUUAUAAUAUUUAAUAUUCUCAACAGUAAAGUAAGAGCACACUAUCACUGCCAUGUUUAUACACAGGGCAUGUUAUUUCAUGGUGGAUGAUACGAACAGUUGACCUCAACAACUAUUUGUUAGAUUAAACGUAUAUAACCCAGGAUUUAUUUGAGUUCCUUUUUAAUGUAUUAUUGAUUCCUACACGAUGACUAUCAGCACUGUUUCUGGCUUUACCUGGAAUGCCAUAAGUACCACCACCAGCCCACACAGAUAUACAUACACACACACACACACACACACUCACAUUCAUAAACACACUUAUUAACUCUUGAUAAUCUAGCAACAACAGUGUACCUCCUCCAGUCUUCUCUGGCUUCCCCAUGCUGCACUAAGAGCCCCAAAUCUACUAAAGCAUUCCAUUCAUAAUUUACUAAUAAUAGAUUUAUUACAUCAUUUUGCAAUCGUUUGUUUACAUUUAGUCCCCUAUUAAAAUAUGAGCUGCUUAAGAUCAGGAGCUAUAAUUUAUACCUCUUGCUACCUUCAGCAACCCACCACAUUGGAUAUGCUCAAUUAAUAUAAAAUUGAAUCUAUCAAUUUUAGAAUCUAUUUGAAGGGAGAAAAAUAAAAAUAACCUGUGGUAAUUUUUUUCAACUGCCAAACUUAUCUGGUACCUGAUAGUAUAGAAAUAAAUUGAAAUCUCAAUUCAUGGAGUGAAAAAAGGAUCUCUAAAGUCCCAUCCAGCUCUAAAAUCUGAUAAUUCUAGAAGUUGGAGCAGAUAACUUCCAAAAUAAGGUAAUUUAAUCUAGUUGCAUCCUCUUUUCAAAAUACAGAAAUGUUAGAUUCAAAAAGCAUAUUAAAAAUAACUAAUGCUUAACCAAGUUUGAAAGAAAGAAGUUUUUUGAUGUCAGAAAUGAAAAGGACCUGAAAGGCACAGCUUUUAGGCCCGUGGGAUACCCAGUAUCAAUAUAAGCCCCAAGAACUCAGGUUUUGGAAUACAUAUAGGAAUAGAAGACAUAGCUUUGGAUCUUAUGGGUGGGAGUUCUAAUUAAGACCUCUUUAUGAAGUGACCGUCUCAAGGAACUCCGCUCCAUGAAAUGACAAGACAUAACUUCCCGCCAAAUUAGGGAAGCUACAGAGGAGAUUGUCAUUGGCCUGGUUAUUCUUGAUGAAGGAAGAAAAAUCUGUUACAGACAGAGUUGUUCAGUGGAAAGUCUGGGGUAAGUUCCUGAUUUAGAACAGGCUUUAGUGCACUUUAAAAGGAAAACAAUGAAUUAUAUAAAACUUUUAGAGGACACAGUGGUGCCAGAUUUUUGUUGGAUUCCUGUGCUUUCCUCCUCCAAAUAGUUACCAAAAAAUAUUCCUUUGGGAAUUAGUAUCAAAAGGAUUCUAUAGCAUCUCAAAAGAAUCUUAUUCACUUUGGGAGGCCGAGGCAGGCAGAUCACAAGGUCAGGAGAUCGAGACCAUCCUGGCUAACACGGUGAAACCCCAUCUCUACUAAAAAUACAAAAAAUUAGCCAGGCGUGGUGGUGGGCGCCUGUAGUCCCAGCUACUCGGGAGGCUGAGGCAGGAGAAUGGCGUGAACCCAGGAGGCAGAGCUUGCAGUGAGCCGAGAUCGCUCCACUGCACUCCAGCCUGGGAGACAGAGUGAGACUCCGUCUCAAAAAAGAAAAAAAAAAAUCUUAUGCAGUAGUCUUAUUUAAUAAAAUCCACUACAAGGAGAGAAGACUGCUGCCUUGACUAUAUAGAAAGGGUUGGCAGAUAUUUCAUUCUAUCAGUUGUAACUAGUAAUCCCAUUGUUAUACAUGCUGACCCAAAAUAUAGCUGUUAUUAACCAAAUAAUGCAUUUUUCUUGAUAAAUGUUGAUUAAAUCAGAUUGGAAGCAAAAUGGUAAUAUUUAUGAUCAAUUUUAGUUUGGAUGUUCAAUGUCAAGACCAAACCCUCUUCACAGCUACCAACUUCAAUUUUAUGUGGAAAACUAAUGGUGAAGAGUUUCAAACUUUAACUGACACUUGACAUUUAACAGGGUAUGUAAUUGCUCACACACAACCUUUAGGUUUUGUAAUCCAGUUUUAUCUCAUACAAUAUUAGAAACAGUACACAUUGUAAAUACCUAUUUUAAAAGUUAGCCAUAUUUUAUAAAGUCACAUGUAUUUAUAUCUUUUCUGAGUAAUUUUCCUGUUAAUGCCUUAUGAUAGGUGCUUGUAACAUGAAAACUAAACUUGGAUCUUGGCAUAUUCAGUGUUCUAUAGAUAGAUUGUGAUCUGUAUAGCUUCUACGGUGACUUUCAGGCCUAAUGUCUCCUUUUAAGUUGUUAUUCUUUAAUAUCCUUUCUCAUUCCUUUCAGAGGACCUAUUAUUAGUUUGCAUUGUCUGCAGCAUUUCAAUAAUACUGUUCUAUUCUAAUAAUACUGAUCUGUUCUAAUAAACAGUUCUAAAUAC